AAUCCAGAAGGAAAAUAAACCCUUUUCAUGUUUUUAAAAUGCAUUGUGUGUACAUAUUGGCAUGUGUGUGUGCUCACACAUAUGUUUGAGUAAGGUGGGAUUGUGUUCAGAAAGAAAGAUUUACUACUAAUACUAAAGGCAAGAGAUGGCAAAAGGCUUUUAUUUACUUCUCUGCCCCUUCCUCAGCCUUCUCUUUUUAAAACUCGUAUAGAAAAUAUGUUAAUCGUGGAACUUUGUCCACAAAGGAUAGAGUAAGAGCCAUUUCCAUUUCAGAAAUUGUUUUUAAUGUUUUGGCCCUGAGUUGGAUCUGGUUCAAGGGUAAAGACGGAAAGAAAAAAAGAUUUGUCUAGGAAGUGAGGCAAUGGAUUGGGAGGUAGAAUAACUGCUAAAGGCAGUCUUGAAGCUAGGAGAGGUAGGGAAUGAUGGAGAAAACCCAGACCCUUGGCCAUCACAUCCAAGGUCCUUCCUUUAAGGACAGAUAGCCAGAGUCCUCAUUGUAAAACAGUAAGUGAGUUGAGUUGAGAGAUCUCAAGCAGGACUAGUUGGGAGUGACCAGAAAAGAAAGAUGAGCAAAAGCAUGACAUACAGCAGCCGGGGAAAAGGCAUUUGGUGACCUGAAGCUAUUAUUCCCGGGUGGCUGUAGAUGUGUGGAGGAUACUCUGAGGUCACGCAAGGAUCUGCCACACAUGAUGUCAUUUCCAAGUCGGUCAGAAGCUUGCUGUGCAGGGCAUAUUUCAGCCCUUGCUGCCCUGUAGCAGGUGUAGGGAAUAGAACAUGUUAAAACAAGGGGCCUGCUUAGGAGAUCCACCACCUUUCCAUUUGAUUUGGAUCAAUGAAUGGCUUUAUGUUCUAGAAUGCUUUUCCCUUGUGGAAGUUUUGUACUUUGUUUGACAGAUUCUAACUGUUUUCUACUUAGAAGAAAAUGGAAUAGGUUUUAUUCUUGAAAUGUACCUGUUGCUGGGAUUCAAAUUCCUAAAACAGAAGUUGCCAUUCCUUUCUCCUCUAAACGAUCUGAUUUGAGAAUGGGAGUUUGAGCAAACAUAAGCUUUACUGCAGAUAGAUUUUUUUUGUUCUCUUUUUCAAAGAGCAGAAAAUUACACAUAAUGCAAUAAUUGUUUUUUUUUUUUGUUUUUGGUUUUUUUUUUUUGCCAUGAAGACAAAAUUACUAAGGAGGAAAAGCUCUAUGAGAAAAUAUAAAUCCUAUUGUAGAGAACACAAUUAGAAGAGGGUAAUUCAAGACACAUCAAUAUAUUGCCAUCUGUAGCAAUCAUUAACUUGUUUCUCUUGCUGUUUAUGAUUCAAAAAGUAGUAUCCUUUCACAAGAAUACUAAAUCACAAUAGAUAAAUAAAUCAUCAGAUUGGAAUACAGAUGGAAUACUGAAGAACAGUAUCAUUCAAGUGAUGGGAAGAAAAGCCAUAUCUUAUAAAAGAUCUUACAGAAAAGCAGCAAGAAUGUGGAAACCAGCAGGAAAUCUACAUAGGUGUUUGGUUUAGAUAAGUCAAGAAAACAACUAAUAACCAUAAAUCAUAAUUAUGAAAAAAUUAUGCCAGAAACUAUAGUAAUUAAGUCCUUUGCAAAUAUAAUCUCACUUAAUCGCCACAGCAUGCCUAUAUGUCACAUGUUAUUAUCUCAUUUAUAAAUAAUCAGGCUUAAAGAGAUUAACUAACAUAUCUCACUGCUAGUAACGGGAGUAUUGGGUUUGAACAGCCAGUAAAGAUGAACUGUAAUAAUAUGAAUAGCUAAGAAGUCAGAUGUUUGGUUGAUCUAUGAUGGAAAAGUUUAAACAAAAAUAUGCUGGAAGUGUAGUGUAGCAACUGAAACAUGAAAGCCAUUGGUAUGAAAGACAAAGGUUCCUAGGCUAGAUAUUGGAGAAGGAAUUACAACUGGAAAAAAACUGUUCUGAAUGAGGCUAAAAACAUGAUAUAGAGAGAUAAAAAAGCAGACUGUAACUCAAAGAAGCUUGUGGACAGAGUGAAUGAGUUUAGGACUUCAGAAGCGGAGUGCUUCCUGCUAAAAUGGAGGCUCAGGGUGUGACCCUGUGCAGGUUAAUACAUACUAAAUGUAUUGCAUGUGGGUUUCCUCUUUGUGAGGACAAUGUAGCAAAUACUUAUGAUGCCUAGUAAAUUAAUUUAUAUUCAUAUUGGACUAAAAUAUUGACUUUUAAAACAACAUUAAUUAUUAUAGUAAUUAAUCAUUAUAAUCAACUCAUUAAAGGUAAAUCUUGGUGAAUAAUGAUUCUGGAAGUCUAUUAAAUUUCAUUUUCACUUUGUUCUAUUUUGCUAACCAUUCACUGAUGUUCCCCCCUCCUGAGAGGUAUUUAAGUGAUAGAGGGACAAACAAACUCCUCAUUUCCUUUUGGUUACAUAAAAUAUAAUAUUGUGAAAUUAUUUUGUUUAUUGAGGGGGCACUUGUAAAAAAAAAAUUAUAAUAUGGAAUUUUUGUUGAUUAUAAUUUAAUUCCAAGAAAGUAUGAGGAACCUCAUGAAACUUUGUUUUGUUUUGAGAUGUGGUCUGUCUCCCAGGCUGAGGUGCAGUGGCAUGAUAUUGGCUCACUGCAGGUUGAACACUCCAGCUAAGUGAUCCUCAUACCUCAGGUUCUCAAGUAGCUGGGAUUACAGGCACAUGUCACCAUGCCCAGCUCAUUUUUAAUUUUUUUUUUGGGGAGACAAGGUCUUGCUAUUUUACCCAGGCUGGUCUCAAACUUCUGGGCUCAAGUGAUCCUCCUGCCUUGGCCUUCAAAGUGCUGAGUGUAUAGGAGUGAGAAGUUGCGUCUGGCCUGAAACAUUUUUCAUACUUAUUUAUUUUCGGUUACCAGGUCCAGCAUGUAAUAUAAAGAUGCUGUAUACAUAUUUAAUAUUUUAAUUUACUUUCUAAAAAAUAUAAUGGAAAUGAGAUUAAUUUGAAUAUUUAUGUUUUAGGUUUUCUCAUUGAUUAGGCAGCGUUAGACAGCUAUUAUAGGAAUUUUGGGGUUUAAUACUACAUCCUCCGCUCAUCUCCCACCAACAAAUGAAAGGAAGAAAAAAAGAAAGAACACUCACUGCCUCCACUUUGUUAAUUGUGACUAUACUAAAUGAUUGGUUGUCUGGGCCAUUUUUCGGGAUGAAAAUUCAACAGAUAAAAACAAUGUAAUUCAUUUUUUAUGGUGUAAUUUUCAAACGUUCAUUAUAAAGUUAUAUUAUUCUAUAAAUUCUCAUUUUGCUUUCUUCAAUAAAAUAUUUGAUGUAUACAAAUAUACAAAGUAUAUAUGUAAAUUAUAAAAGCAUAAUGUAAUAUAAACUACAUGUACCUCGUACCCAACUUAAAAAAUUAAACAUUAUCUUUCACUUUUAAAAUAAUUUGUGCUUCUCCCUGCUGGUCAUAUCCCCUUGCCUCUCUGUCAGAAGUAAUCACAAUAAAAAAAGUUUUAUUAUGAAAUAGCAUAGCAUAUACAUAAACAUAGUAACCUCCCAUUACUUAUUUUUCCACUCCCUAUUAUGUGUCUGAGAUCCAUCCAUGUUGACACAUUUAGCUGCAUUCCUUUCUUAUUGUGCUGUGUAGCUAAUCUGCUGUGUGAAUAGACCAUAGGGUACAGGUCUAUUCCACUGUAGAUGGAUAUCUGGAUCCAUGCUUUUGCUGUUACAAAGACUUCUGUUAAUAAUGCUCUUGCACAUGCCUACUUGUCCACAGCUGCAUGAGUCUUUACAGUCUAGCAUGAGUCUUUACAGUCUAUUACCUAGAAAAGAAAUUGCUGGGUCUUAUAGUACUAGGAUCAUGACUUCAGUAGAAGUUACCAAAGAGUGCUACUAAUUUUUACUCCCACCUAGAUGUAUAAGAGUUCUUUUUGUUCUACAUCUUCAUCAGUGGUUGCUACUGUUAUACAUUUUUUUAAAUGUAUGUAAAUCUUUCAGAUGAAAAGUAGAAUCCAAAAGUAAUUUUGAUUUUUUUUCACUAAAUAUCCUAGAUACUAAGAAGAAUUUUAUGUUUAUUGGUAUGUUUUCUUUUCUGUGAAAUAUCCAUUUUCUCUUAGAAUAUGAUUUUCUUACUGAAUUGUUGGAGUUCUUUAUAUUUGAAGGAUAUUAAUCCUUUGUCAUAUUUGUAACUUGUCUUUUUGUUCUUUUUACAGUGACUUUGCAUGAACAAAUGUCCUUAGUUUCAAAGCUGUUGCAAGCUUUUUUUGUCUUAUGUAAAAAAUAUUUUCCUACAGUAAGGCCAUUAAAAUAUUUUUCUUCACUCUUAUAAGGUAAAAAUUUUGCUUUUCGCAUUUAAGUCUAUGAUCUACUAGAAAUUUUUGUAUAGGGUACAAAAUUCAUUUCUUUAUUUUUAAGAGUAAACAAACAAUUGUCCCAGCUCAUUCAUUGAUUUGUCUUUUCUGUCUCCACUGAAUGACAAUGACAUAUCUUCCUCAGGUAAACUCCGACUGCAGGGUCUUUGCACUUGCUUGGGCCUUUGCCUGAAGUGCUCUUCCCUCAGGCAGCGACAUGCUCCCUUCUGUACUUCCUUCAGCCUUUUUCUCUAAAGUCAUUUUUUUCAGUGAGGCCACAUAUGGCCAUUUAUAUCUAAAAUUCAAUACUUUUCCAAACUUUUGCAAUACCACAUCCCUUAUUUUUUCCAAUACUCUUGUGACUAUUUGAAUUUGUGUAUACUUGUCUUAUUUAUCUUAUUGUGUCUCUCUCCCACUAAAACACAAACACAAUAAGGAAAAUGAUUUUUGUUGGUUUUAUUUACUGCUGAAACCCCAAAACCUAGAAAAAUGCCUAGCACAUAAUAAAUGCUCAGUAAUACUAAUUGAGUGAGUGGAUGUAUGAGCAUAUUACAUUUGAAAAUGGAUCUGCUUGUAGGCUUCAGAUCUGUUGGAGUGGCCUAUUUCUUUUUCUCUGGGUGAGUGCCAGUAACUUAAUCCAUAGCUGUAAAAUAAGGCUUGAUGUCUAGUAGGUCAUGGCCUCUACAUGUUCUCAUUCUUUAAGGGUGGUUUAUCUAUUCUUGAUAACUUCCUCUCCUAUGUAAAUUUUAGAAUUAUGCUUUCAAGUCUUAUGAAAAAUCAUAUUAUACUUUAUUCACAUGGCAUUUACUCUAUAAAUUUUAAGAAAACAGACUUUUAAAAAUUAUUUUUAAUGUUUCUAUCCAUAAAUGUACGUCUUAGUUUUUUCUUUAAUGUCUUUAUAUAUAUUGUAUAUGUUAUCUCUAUAAGGUUAUAUACUGUUUGAUAAAUGCUUAUUAUUCUUACAGACAUAGUUAAGUUUUUCAUACAUUCUUCUAUUAAAUCAGGUCUUUACACAUUAACAUUAUGCAUUCUAAAAAUUAAAUCAUAAAAUAUGAAUUUGUAAAUAAAGGUAAAUUUUUGAAAGCAGCUAGUAAUUAAUCAGAAAUUUUCCAUUUAGCUAUGAGAUGAAAGUCUUAAAAGUUGAACCUAAUAAAACUACUGAGAAAGCUUGAGGAAAACAACUUUGCUCUUAACUUGUAACUUUUCUCCCACUAUAAAGCCUUAUUAUGACCCAUCCCCAACAACAUUAUUUCCUCCCUUGUGUUUCUAAUUAUGAUUCUGUUUUACAGCAAUUAUCAUAAUAUCGUGUUCUGUGGUAUUUAUCUCUACAUACAUUUGUCAUCCCCACUAGACUGCACACUCAUUGAGACCAGGAACUUUAUCUUGUCUUUUUAUCCUCAGGCUUAGUCACAGUGCCUGCCAUGGACUACAUGCUUAUAAUGUAGUCAUUAUAAACUGAUGGGCACUAAAAUUGGGCAUCCAAAGGAGAUAAUAGAACCUACCUUUUUAAAAACCUUCAAAAAUUGCACAGAAAUUGGCCUGUCUGAUAAUCCCUUUUUUCUCAGUCCUCUUUCCCUUUAGAUAUGUAUCCCAUUCUCUCCUAUUUCUCCUCCCACUCUCACCUUUUCAGGCUCCUUUGUUGGAUCUUUUUUCUCUGCCAUCCCUGAAAACAUCAGUGCUUUCCCAGGAAUGGUAGCCCUGUUUCUUCUAACGUUACUCAAAGUCUGUUACAUAUCAUUCACUCUUAUGUCUUCAGUUAUACCAAUAAUUCUUAUAUUUAACCUCAACACUGAACACAUUUUAAAACUCUUCAACCUUAUUUUAAGUUUCUUACAUAUCUACUACACAUCUCAUAAACCUGCUAAAAGCAUAUAAAAUUUAAUGUUCCUAAUAUGAACUAAUUCCCUUGUCUACACAUCCUUCUAAAAUUUGCCAUUCUUCCUUUAUUCAUAUGAUGGUCUGUGUUGUCACUAUUCAUUCAGUUACCCAAAUGAGAAGAAUGAGCCUGGGGCCUUAUUUCAAAAAGGUAUUGCUGACUUAAAAGCCUGUAUCCUAAAAAUGUCCCCAGUCUCUCCUUCAGUCUUCCAGUUGCUACAGGCUGAAUUAUGUCCUGUAUUUUUCAGCUGGACUAUUACAAAACGAAACUUCUUGUCUUUUUAACUCCAGAUUGACUUUCUUCCUUCAAUUUCUUGUCCAAAUUAUUUUUUUCUAAAAUACAAACUUUCUUAUGUAUACAUUUGAGUUGAAUGCUCCUUUUCACCUAAUAUUGCUAAAAGGGGAAAAGUCCAAAUUCAUUAACACAGCACACAGGACAAUUCAUCUGCGUGUCCCAAUCUAUCUUGCCACUUUCAUCUCUUCCAGAUAUACUAUUCUCCAUUCAUACCAAAAUUUUAAACGUUUACUGACAUAACAUUCUUUCAUACGUUUACAUGGGUGUUUCUGUUCUAUCAUUUUCUCCUUUCUAAGUAAAUAAUUCCUACUCAUCCAGCUCAAAUAUUAUCACUCAUUUGAAGUCUUCCAGGAUGCCCACAAACUGAGUAAACAACCCCUUUCCUCUGUUCCCAAGUACUUAACUUAUAUCUUUAUUUCAAUACUUGCUAAUUCUAAUUAAAAUAUAUUUAUGUUUUUGUCUACCCUUCAUUACUCUGGGUUAUUUUCUGAAGGUCAGAACCACUUGUUUUGCAUUAUUUUUUCUGCCCAGUUAGGUUACAUAUCCAUCCUUGAACAAAACUCUGCAGCGAUGCAGGAAACAUCUUCUGUCCAUGUAGACAGCAUCCUUCCCGCUUGUCAGCACUGACUGAAUUCCAUCCUUCUUGCAAGCCUACAUGUUCAGCUUCUUCCUUACAACUUUAUCAAACUGCCCAACCUCCUCAAUUUGUCUUUAAUUCAUUGUUUUCAGUUCUUUACUAUAUUAACUAAUCUCUCUACAAUCAAUAUAGAAUAUUCUAAUGAUUAUAUAUUUCAUCAUGACCAUAAGCAUUGGACAUACAGCAUAGGAGUCUAAUAACUUCUCCUGUUUAUUUGGCCCUCAGUAUCUGAAGGAUAAUGGUGUCUGAAAACCGCAAUACCAUUAUGGAUUCUGAACAUGCCUGGCUUUAAGUACUUUGCUUAUAUUAUUUCAUUUAAUCUUCCCAGUAGUCUUUUUCAAGAUAAAAACAGUAAUGGAUGCACUAUUCUGGAAGGCCAAUACAGGCCUACCCACCUCAAUAUUUGUAUUCCAACAUACUUUCUUUUUUUUCCCCUUAGGGACAGAGUCUCCCUCUGUCACCCAGGCUGGAAUGCAGUGGCACAAAUAUAAUUCACUACAGCCUCAAUCCACUGGUCUUAAGUGAUCCUCUCAUCUUAGCCUUUCAAGUAGUUGGGCCUACAGAUGGACCCGAUUCAGAAAGCUGUAAUAAACCAUACAUUCGGGGUUCCUCUUCCCCACCGAAGAAAGCAAAUCAUAUCAUGCAACAUUUGCCAGUUGAGAUUUAAUUCUGAUAGCCAGGCUGCGGCCCACUACAAAGGCACGAAACAUGCCAAGAAGCUCAAAGCACUGGAAGCCAUGAAAAAUAAGCAGAAAUCUGUAACUGCCAAGGACAGCGCAAAGACUACCUUCACCUCCAUCACUACCAAUACCAUCAAUACCAGCUCUGACAAAACAGGGGGAAAAAAAGGUGCAAUGAAGCCCUGUGGUUUAUUCUUACCAUUCUGCACAAGAGACGGUACUGCAGGGACACCAGCAAUAUCAACGACGACAACUGUGGAAAUCCGCAAAAGCAGUGUUAUGACAACUGAGAUCACCUCUAAAGUGGAAAAAAGCCCAACGACAGCCACUGGCAAUAGCUCAUGUCCUUCUACUGAGACCGAGGAAGAAAAGGCAAAACGGCUUCUUUACUGUUCGCUAUGCAAGGUUGCUGUCAACUCUGCCUCGCAGCUGGAGGCGCACAACAGUGGUACUAAGCACAAAACCAUGUUAGAAGCCCGGAAUGGAAGUGGCACUAUCAAAGCCUUUCCUAGGGCAGGAGUGAAAGGCAAAGGACCUGUUAAUAAAGGAAACACAGGCCUCCAAAAUAAAACAUUUCACUGUGAAAUCUGUGAUGUGCACGUCAACUCGGAAACGCAACUUAAACAGCACAUUAGCAGUAGAAGGCACAAAGACAGAGCUGCUGGGAAGCCCCCGAAACCUAAAUACAGUCCUUACAACAAACUACAGAAGACAGCACAUCCACUGGGGGUAAAAUUAGUAUUUUCAAAAGAACCUUCAAAGCCAUUGGCUCCACGAAUUCUACCAAAUCCUCUAGCAGCUGCAGCAGCCGCAGCAGCAGUGGCAGUGAGUUCCCCCUUCAGUCUUCGAACUGCUCCAGCAGCAACACUGUUCCAGACUUCCGCGCUUCCUCCGGCACUCCUGCGGCCAGCUCCUGGACCCAUUCGGACCGCCCACACUCCUGUGCUGUUUGCUCCUUACUAAAUUCCAAAUAGGAGUAAUUGUACUGCAAUAAUUUUUCAAAAAACAAAAAACAAAACAAACAAAAGAGAACUAUGCAGUGUUUAUUUAUAGUUUAAAGUAUAUCUGAAGAGCCAGGACUUUUGAUAGUGAAUUGAAAAGGUUAUAAAAAAGUGGGGGAGGUUUGGGGGUGGGAGGGAGGGAGUGGUAUUUUCUCCAAAUUAAAGCAUUCCUCUUGAACGCUGAUUGUUUUAGAAGUGAUCUCCAGCAUUGAUUUGUAGUGGUAUCUAGACCUUCUGAAGCCUCUGUGACUGUGCUUUUGGGCACCUAUUUCCCUCUGCAUUGUCUGUCCUGCUUUAUGAAACAACUAUACAUUGUCUAAGGGCAUUAACUGGUUCCAAUGUAUAUAAAAUAAUUUACUCUGUAGAUUAAAAUCGUACAAAAAAAAAGGAAAAAAACAAAAACAAAAGCAACACUGUGAAUAGUACUACCCGUGCUGGUCCUCUUGCUAUGACGGCAAUUACUGGGUAUUUAUCCCAACAAAAGUAGAUACAGUAGAUGUCUUGUAAAACAAUAGUGCUGUGUCUCAAUCUAUGCCACUAGGUUUUAAAGAAUUGCAAAGGUAGAAUGAACAACUAUUUCAUACCAAUAAGCAGUCAAAAAAUAAACAUACACCGGAUGGUGUCAUGGAGGUCUCCCUGGUCAGCAUUCUCCCCUCCUGUCUAGCUUGAAGAUAUAACAGGGCUAAGCUUAGAGAUGGGGGAGGCAUUAAUAAAGGUGAUUUCUUAUAAAGUAGUAACUUCCCACCCUGAAGAUAUAUUGCUGGAAACAGGGAAGUGUUUAUAAUGAACCUAUAUCUGAAAGCAGAGAAACCCAUGCAUCAUGAGUGUUAAGAAAGAAAUCAAUACAACUCUUCUAUUUCAAGGAUGAAGAAUCAUAACCUAGAAUGAUAAUGCAAAGUAAAGAUCUUUCAUUUAGUACAUAUCCAGUAAAAACGGAGAAUGUUGCAUCUCUGCAGUAUCCCCUUUAUAUCAUACCAGUAGGGUUGUUUCUUAGGCAAAGGUUUCUGCUUUAAGUAUGAUGGUAGAAUUAAGCAUUAGCUAUUUUUAUGGGUUUUUCUUGUUUUUUAGAUUACCUGCUGACAUGAUAUAAACAAUUAAUAUAUAUUUAAAUGUUAAUAACAACAGGAAAUAUGAAUCUGAGUUAAUUGCACACCAAUGACAUAGUGUUAAAAAAUACUGGUAAGUUCCACUCGACAAUUAUUUCUCCAGUGGAGUUGUGAAAUACUGAGAGCCUUUGAUAUUCACCAUCAGGCUGAAAGAAGUUGAUGUUUUACCUUUAAAACAAGAUUUAUCAGGGGUAUAUAUAAAUAUAUGUAUAUUGUAUAUAUGUUAGAAAGAUUAAGAGAAUAAGUUAUAAAAAGAAAAAAUCUAUAUAAAAUAAUUAUAUAACCAUCCAGUGUUACAUGUUAUCAUUAAAUUGGUAACAAAUGGCAUAAAAAUAGCUGUGCCUUUAAUUUGUGAUAAAGGCUAUUUGCUUUUUCCCAUAGAAAGCUGACAUAUACCUAUCAAAAUGGUGGGGUUUGAUGCAGCCAGUCUGUUGCAUUAAUAAGAGCAAUGACACUGAAACUUAGAAUAAUGACAAAACAUACAUGAUUUAGGUUUAGAGAAAAAACUAUUUUUGAAAAGGUUUUCUAAAGACUAUUUAAAAAUAUAGGGAAGGAUUGGGUGUGGCCUUCCUGAAACUGCUCUCAAAGUGUUGUAACCCUUGGAGAGGUAUAAAGAAUCAAGAGGAAACCAUUUGAGACAUAGGUAUUUAGCAUUUAUCAUUUUAUAUUUAAGAAACACCAUAGCGUGCUUGGUGCUCAACAUUAAACAUGGUUUUUUGGAGUUCUUCUCCACCAUCUAGCUAUAGAAAUUUGUCAUAUAAAUGAAUCUUUAAAGCAGUUGGCUUUAUAUAUCCUUUGUUAACCAACCAAAACAAAAACAAAAAAAAAGAAGGAAAGAAGGAAGGAAGGAAGGAAGAAUGGAAGGAAGGAAGGAAGAAAGGAGGGAAGGAAGGAAGGAAAGGAGAUGGGGAAGGGAAGAAAAGGAAGGAAGGAAGAAAGGAAGAUAAUGUGUUCCAUCAGUAUUCUGGUAGAAAGAAUUUCAAACCAUGCUUCUCUGGUUAAAUAUAUUGAUUAGCAUUAAAAUUUGUUUUGAAAGUAUCUGGUGAUUUUGCAUUUACCAGCAUCUCUAUUCUCUAGUUUUAGCAAGUGUUUCCUUUUUCACCUACAGACCCUGGUAGUUCAGCCAGGUGGAUAGUUGCCCAUAAGUCUGUUGUUUGGGGCUCUGUCUGUAUCCCAUGUGACCAGCUUCUAACCAUUUUGAACUUUAGUUUCCCUUUUCUGCUAUGUCAAAUAUUUUGAUUUUCCAUAAUCAUCCUGAGUCCCUAUCCAACAACCUUUACAACUGAUACAGCCUCACUUUCUGUUAGAUAACUUAGUGUUAAUUAAAGCAGUCUCACUAAAACGUGCUUUUGCUGUUCUUUCCCAUUUUCACCAAAGUGAAUGAGCCAGUCCACUAAAAAUCAGGGCCUAUGGGAUACACAGUGUCCUGGGUCACAAGGCAUUACUGUCUUUAAUGAUUUGCUGGGAACAAACGAAUCAGCCAUAUUUUCUCCAUCAGCCAUAUAAGAAAUCUCAGAAAUACCUGGAUCCCUUCUGCCUCACUUCGCUAUGGAACCAUUUUUGUUUAAAUGGUCUUUUAAAUUGGAGUUGUAAGCAUCAGUUGUCUUUUAUUCACUACCUAAUAAAGGAUGAAGCCUAACCACAGAACUUACAGUGGAUUCUCUGUGAGUUGUUUCCCCCACACUCCAUAUAUUUACCAAUACCAGAUUAACAUCCAUUAUAGUUCAGGCUGCCAUAAAACUGUAUCUUUUCCCUUAGGGAACUUUUUUCAUGAAUAAAGAUCCACAAUUUAGAUUGGUCAGCAGUGUGCUGUGAAAAUCCCUGAGGGUGGUCUGACUUUAUGGUUUUACAUUCCUUCCCAUGCAUCACACCAUGGCAAGGAAAGUGAUAGAGAAAGCAGCUCUGAUUCAUUUGAAACAAAUAUAAAUGCAUUGCAGAAGCCAAAUGCCUCUGGAAAAAGCAUUGUUGCACCUCAAUCAGAUCGUCCAGACAAAUGGGAAACAGUCAUUGGGGAGGUACUGUAUUUCUCUUAUGAGAAAACAGGCAAUUACACAUGAUAAAUUGCUCCUCUCACUGGACCUCAACUUUGAAGAGUACUUUUUUUAUUCACAUAAGCAAACAUACUUGGCUUUUGGCAAUUUAUAUCACCCCUGCCUCAUUUGAAAGGAUUUCUAUCUUUAGGUACUAUUUGGCUUCUCCUGAUCUAUCGCAGUAAUUCACUGCCAUUAUCAUCAGAGAUGAAAUUUGGUUUUUCUAAAGGUGCUACAUAUUUUGUUGCCAAGAAACUAGUUAGCAAAGGAGUAUUUAUAUGUACUUGAAAAUUAAAAGAGCAGGAAAUCAUAAAAGACUAAGAAUUAAAAGACAGCAGAAGUUUCAAAAUAGAAUCAAAGAGGCUGUGCCUAUUUGAGUUUCUAAGGCACAAACCAACACAUAGUAGACAUGAGCAAUAAAUAUCACCAAUUACAAUUAAAUUUUAAAUUAAUAUCUUUGUCUUUGUACCAGUGUAAUGUUUCAAUUGUUCUGAAGAAAUCAGAUCAGAAAGCUAAAAGGUAACUGAAGUGGUAUAUAGGCCUGUUUCUUUAGAUCUGAAUUGAAGUAGAAAAUUACCUUUCUAUACAUAAGCAUGGAUGACAUUGUAUUAAUAACUUUGUUCACCCAAAAGCCGCAUGAAGUGGUGGGAAAAGCAAUGAGGAGCCUUAGAGUAGCCAGAGUCUAUUGUAGACUUUGUCCCUGACCAACAGGGUAACUUAAAUAGUCAACUAAUGCCUUGCCCUUAAUUUCUUCAUCAGUAAAAUGGAUGACAGUGAUUAAUAGCUAAGCUGGUUUAAUACAUCAGCACUAGAGGGGCAUUGCUUUUAUCCUCUCAGGAAUAAAAAUUCUUUAUUCGAGUGACCAAUGCAGCUACUCACAUACUUGCAUAUGUCCAGAAAAAUAUUCUGUAUUCCUUUCCAUCCUGAGUGUAAGCCAUAUUGUAGGUCAUUCAUAUGCUCAACCAGAAUGUACAUUUCACCAAUAUUGGAGUAGUUGCUAAUUCACUUAGUACUCACUUAUUAUGAUCGCACUUAUGCCAACAUCAUGUAAGAUAUGCUACUUCUAUUUUCCCAGUCAAGAAUGUAAUAAAUUCUGAACAAAACCAACCCUGAAAAAGGCAAUAGACAGCUGGCAGUGGGGGUGUGGAAGGGAACAACAAUUUAAAUGCAUCAUCCUUAUUUCUUUUGUUGCACUUUCUCUCUUCAAUAGGAAGGGGUCCCGACUAAGCCAUAACUAAUUCUGUCCUGCGUUUGCAUGUAUUUUAACUAAUGGUUGCCUUAUUAAGACCAUCUCUUCCACAGACAAGUAUAUCAGUUAUGCGCUCUUGUCAUUGUUACAGGAAUUAUUUAAACUGAGUCCUAACAGUGAAAGUUUUACCUGACUUUUGCUGAUUUUUUUUUCUUUCUACAUGGGGAGAUUUAUCUCUGGAGCAUCUCUUGUGUUUUUGUAUGGUUUGCUUCAGUAGCUAGAGAGGCUACUAUCAGGAAGUGAAAUGGAUCAUUUCUAAUGGUAGGUCUCCAUUGCCUACAUGGUAUUUCUGAGAGUGGUAUCAGGGUGUCCAGUGAAAGACGGAUAGGUUGACAUGUCAUGCUCAUUUGGCCUAAAGGUUGUUACUGCCAGGAAUGGACUUACAACUUACCAGAAUGUGAAUGGUGACAAAAGGCAGGUUCUACUCUGGAAAAAUAUGUGUUAUUUUAUUAGAAG